AGUUAGAGCAACAAGAUGGCCGCGGUGGCAGCUCCGCACCUCAGCGCGACGGCCCCGGGAGCCGUAGCCGCCGCCGCCGGCCCCGCCGCCGCGCAGUCUUGAGCGCCGCCCGGGCCGCCCCCUGACAGGGCAGUCCCAGCGCCCGCCGCGCUCCCGCCGCCGUCACCGUCGCAGUAGCCGCGGGCCCGCCCGAGCCGGAGGCGGAGGGAGCGGAGCGGCCCCGCGCCCAGCCGUCCGCAGCUGCCACCGCCGCCGCCGCCGCCGCCUAGGACCCGGACCCCGCCGGAGCCGCAUCCCGCCGGGCGUGAGGAGGAGGACGCGUCGCGGCGUUGCCGGGGCCGGACCUGGACCUGCCGGGACGCGCCGCCGCCCACUCGCCCGCGCCGCCGCCGCAGCCGCCGCCGCCGCCCGCGCCGGGACCUGAGUCCGUGGCGCCGGCGCUGAGCGGGCCCCCGCCGCCCGCGCACUCCCGAGGCCCUCGGGCGGUUGUUCGUGCCGCCGCCGCCGCCAGGCCCGCGCCACCGGAGCCCCGCGGAGCCGCCGCCGCCGCCGGGGACGGAGCCCAGGGAGAAAGAGCAAGAAACACAAGAAGAGGAACGUUUGAUGGAAGAAAAGAAAAAGAAAAAGCAGGAAGAAAAGAAAAAGAAGGAAGGUGCUCAGAAAAAGGCUGCUGAUCAAAAAACCAAAGUGCCAGAACCUACUAAGACCUGUUCAAGCCAGCCCCAACCUGCCGGUACCAGUACCAGUACUUCCACCAGCACUAUCUCAAGCAGCAACAAUGGCAAACGUGCAUCUGCCAGUGGCCAGCAGCCAGCUGCAUCCCGUUACCUGCCUCGUGAGGUGCCUCCACGCUUCCGCCAGCAAGAACAGAAGCAGCUAUUAAAGAGAGGCCAGCCAUUGCCUACGGGGACUCUAACCAGUGUGAGCCCAACCCAGGGUGCUGGGCCUGCAGGGGUAAGCCCACCUCCCCUACCUGGAGCCGGAACACAGCAUCAUCCCAGUAAGCUCCAACCAGAUCUCAGUCAUAGUGGAUUGGCAGAUCAUUAUGAAAAUUCCCACUGGGGACAGCAGCCUACUUACAGAAGCGAAGCCAACUGCAGCUGGGAUAAAGUGAUAAUAGAUAGGACUGACAAGGAGGCGUGGCCUUCCAUCACAGGAACAGAGACUGAAUCUGCCUCAGAAUGUACUACAGACACUGACUCUGCCUCCAACUGUGGCUCAGAGAACAGUAGCAUGGCUACAGGGAGUGCCCAGGGCAACUUCACUGGACAUACCAAGAAGACAAAUGGCAAUAAUGGCACCAAUGGCGCACUCGUCCAAAGCCCUUCUAAUCAGAGUGCCCUUGGAGCAGGGGGAGCGAACAGUAAUGGAAGUGCGGCCAGAGUGUGGGGUGUAGCCACAGGCUCCAGCUCUGGCCUGGCUCACUGCUCUGUCAGUGGUGGGGAUGGAAAAAUGGACACUAUGAUUGGAGAUGGGAGAAGUCAGAAUUGCUGGGGUGCUUCCAACUCCAAUGCUGGCAUUAAUCUUAACCUUAAUCCUAAUGCCAACCCAGCUGCCUGGCCUGUACUUGGACAUGAAGGAACCGUGGCGACAGGCAACCCUUCCAGUAUUUGCAGUCCAGUCAGUGCCAUAGGUCAAAAUAUGGGCAACCAGAACGGGAACCCAACAGGCACUUUAGGUGCUUGGGGAAACUUGCUGCCACAAGAGAGCACAGAACCACAAACGUCCACUUCUCAGAAUGUGUCUUUCAGCGCACAACCUCAGAACCUUAACACUGAUGGACCAAAUAACACUAACCCCAUGAACUCUUCACCCAACCCUAUCAAUGCAAUGCAGACAAAUGGACUGCCAAACUGGGGCAUGGCUGUUGGUAUGGGGGCCAUCAUCCCGCCCCACCUGCAAGGCCUUCCUGGUGCUAAUGGAUCAUCAGUUUCUCAAGUCAGUGGGGGCAGUGCUGAAGGAAUAAGCAAUUCUGUGUGGGGACUGUCCCCAGGUAACCCUGCCACAGGAAAUAGCAAUUCUGGGUUCAGUCAGGGGAAUGGAGACACUGUGAACUCAGCAUUAAGUGCUAAACAAAAUGGAUCCAGCAGUGCUGUGCAAAAGGAAGGAAGUGGAGGAAAUGCUUGGGAUUCAGGACCUCCUGCUGGUCCUGGAAUACUCGCCUGGGGAAGGGGCAGUGGCAACAAUGGCGUUGGUAAUAUCCAUUCAGGAGCUUGGGGCCACCCCAGCCGAAGCACCUCUAACGGUGUGAAUGGGGAAUGGGGAAAGCCCCCAAACCAGCAUUCCAACAGUGACAUCAAUGGGAAAGGAUCAACAGGGUGGGAGAGUCCUAGUGUCACCAGCCAGAACCCUACCGUACAGCCUGGUGGUGAACACAUGAACUCCUGGGCCAAAGCGGCAUCUUCUGGAACUACAGCAAGUGAAGGAAGUAGUGAUGGUUCUGGCAACCACAAUGAAGGAAGCACUGGGAGGGAAGGAACGGGAGAAGGCCGAAGGCGAGAUAAAGGGAUUAUAGACCAAGGGCACAUCCAGUUGCCAAGGAAUGAUCUUGACCCAAGAGUUCUGUCUAAUACUGGUUGGGGACAGACUCCUGUAAAGCAAAACACUGCCUGGGAAUUUGAAGAAUCCCCUAGGUCUGAAAGGAAAAAUGACAAUGGGACAGAGGCCUGGGGUUGUGCAGCUACUCAGGCUUCAAACUCAGGGGGGAAGAACGAUGGGUCCAUCAUGAACAGUACAAAUACCUCUUCAGUAUCUGGGUGGGUCAACGCGCCACCUGCCGCUGUGCCAGCAAACACAGGUUGGGGAGACAGCAACAACAAAGCGCCAAGUGGCCCGGGGGUUUGGGGGGACUCGAUAAGCUCUACUGCUGUUAGUACUGCUGCUGCUGCCAAGAGUGGCCAUGCUUGGAGUGGGGCCGCAAAUCAGGAGGACAAGUCACCCACCUGGGGUGAGCCUCCAAAGCCCAAAUCCCAACACUGGGGAGAUGGACAAAGAUCAAAUCCAGCCUGGAGUGCAGGAGGGGGAGAUUGGGCAGAUUCAUCGUCUGUCCUUGGACACUUGGGGGAUGGGAAAAAAAAUGGAUCUGGAUGGGAUGCUGACAGUAAUAGGUCAGGGUCUGGUUGGAAUGACACCACGAGAUCUGGGAACAGUGGCUGGGGCAACAGCACAAAUACAAAGGCCAAUCCAGGUACAAACUGGGGGGAGACUUUAAAACCUGGCCCCCAACAGAACUGGGCUAGCAAACCCCAAGACAACAAUGUGAGUAACUGGGGAGGAGCUGCUUCUGUGAAACAGACAGGAACAGGGUGGAUCGGGGGGCCGGUACCGGUCAAACAGAAGGACAGCAGUGAAGCAACUGGCUGGGAAGAACCCUCUCCACCGUCCAUUCGCCGCAAAAUGGAAAUUGAUGAUGGUACCUCAGCUUGGGGGGACCCAAGCAACUAUAACAAUAAAACUGUAAACAUGUGGGAUAGAAACAACCCGGUCAUCCAGAGCAGUACCACGACCAAUACCACCACCACCACCACCACUACCACGAGCAACACCACACACAGGGUCGAGACGCCGCCCCCGCACCAGGCCGGUACUCAGCUGAAUCGAUCACCGUUGCUUGGUCCAGUUUCAUCAGGCUGGGGAGAAAUGCCUAAUGUUCACUCAAAGACUGAAAACUCUUGGGGAGAACCAUCCUCCCCUUCUACCCUGGUGGAUAAUGGCACAGCAGCAUGGGGGAAGCCACCCAGCAGUGGCAGCGGGUGGGGAGAUCACCCUGCAGAGCCGCCGGUGGCAUUUGGAAGAGCUGGCGCACCUGUUGCUGCCUCAGCCCUGUGCAAACCAGCUUCAAAAUCUAUGCAAGAAGGCUGGGGCAGUGGUGGGGAUGAAAUGAACCUCAGUACCAGCCAGUGGGAGGAUGAAGAAGGGGACGUGUGGAAUAAUGCUGCUUCCCAAGAAAGCACCUCCUCCUGCAGCUCCUGGGGGAACGCCCCCAAAAAAGGACUUCAAAAGGGCAUGAAGACGUCUGGCAAGCAGGAUGAGGCCUGGAUCAUGAGCCGGCUGAUCAAACAACUCACAGACAUGGGCUUCCCGAGAGAGCCAGCUGAGGAGGCCUUGAAGAGUAACAAUAUGAAUCUUGAUCAGGCCAUGAGCGCUCUGCUGGAAAAGAAGGUGGACGUGGACAAGCGUGGGCUGGGAGUGACCGACCAUAAUGGAAUGGCCGCCAAGCCCCUCGGCUGCCGCCCGCCAAUCUCCAAAGAGUCUUCCGUGGACCGCCCCACCUUUCUUGACAAGGAUGGCGGCCUCGUGGAAGAGCCCACGCCUUCACCGUUCUUGCCUUCCCCAAGCCUGAAGCUCCCCCUUUCACACAGUGCACUCCCCAGUCAGGCCCUGGGUGGGAUUGCCUCCGGGCUGGGCAUGCAAAACUUGAAUUCUUCUAGACAGAUACCGAGUGGCAAUCUGGGUAUGUUUGGCAAUAGUGGAGCAGCACAAGCCAGGACCAUGCAGCAGCCGCCACAGCCACCAGUGCAGCCUCUUAACUCUUCCCAGCCCAGUCUCCGUGCUCAAGUGCCUCAGUUUCUAUCCCCUCAGGUUCAAGCACAGCUUUUGCAGUUUGCAGCAAAAAACAUUGGUCUCAACCCUGCACUAUUAACCUCGCCAAUUAAUCCUCAACAUAUGACGAUGUUGAACCAGCUCUAUCAGCUGCAGCUGGCAUACCAACGUUUACAAAUCCAGCAGCAGAUGUUACAGGCCCAGCGUAAUGUGUCCGGAUCCAUGAGACAACAGGAGCAGCAAGUUGCGCGCACAAUCACUAAUCUGCAGCAGCAGAUCCAGCAGCACCAGCGCCAGCUGGCCCAGGCCCUGCUCGUGAAGCAGCCACCACCGCCACCGCCCCCGCCGCACCUGUCUCUGCACCCCUCUGCAGGCAAAUCGGCCAUGGACAGCUUCCCCUCGCACCCACAGACUCCCGGCCUACCUGACCUGCAGACCAAAGAGCAGCAGUCUUCACCCAACACCUUUGCUCCUUACCCUCUCGCUGGACUGAACCCAAACAUGAAUGUCAACAGCAUGGACAUGACCGGUGGCUUGUCGGUGAAGGACCCAUCCCAGUCCCAGUCACGCCUCCCCCAGUGGACGCACCCCAACUCCAUGGAUAACUUGCCCAGUGCCGCUUCCCCCCUGGAGCAGAACCCUAGCAAGCAUGGUGCUAUCCCUGGAGGUCUAAGCAUUGGGCCUCCAGGUAAGUCCUCCAUUGAUGACUCCUAUGGCCGGUACGAUUUAAUCCAGAACAGUGAGUCACCAGCCAGUCCUCCCGUAGCUGUUCCCCAUAGCUGGUCACGUGCCAAAUCUGACAGUGAUAAAAUCUCAAAUGGCUCUAGCAUCAACUGGCCCCCAGAAUUCCAUCCGGGAGUUCCAUGGAAAGGACUGCAGAAUAUUGACCCUGAGAAUGACCCUGACGUCACUCCUGGCAGUGUCCCCACUGGGCCUACCAUCAACACCACCAUCCAGGAUGUCAACCGCUACCUCCUCAAGAGUGGAGGGUCCUCCCCGCCAUCAUCUCAGAAUGCCACGCUGCCUUCUUCGAGUGCCUGGCCACUCAGUGCCUCCGGCUACAGUAGCUCUUUCAGCAGCAUUGCAUCCGCACCUAGUGUUGCAGGUAAACUGUCAGACAUCAAAUCGACGUGGUCCUCUGGCCCUACCUCCCACACGCAAGCCUCUCUGUCUCAUGAACUAUGGAAGGUGCCCAGAAACAGUACUGCACCCACGAGGCCACCUCCAGGGUUAACCAAUCCCAAGCCCUCCUCCACCUGGGGUGCCAGCCCCCUCGGCUGGACCAGCUCCUACUCCUCGGGUUCUGCCUGGAGCACCGACACCUCAGGAAGAACCAGCAGCUGGCUCGUUCUUCGAAACCUCACUCCCCAGAUUGAUGGUUCUACACUGCGGACAUUGUGUUUGCAACAUGGGCCUCUUAUCACAUUCCACCUGAAUCUGACUCAAGGCAAUGCUGUGGUCCGGUACAGCUCCAAGGAGGAGGCUGCCAAGGCCCAGAAGUCUCUGCACAUGUGCGUCCUGGGAAACACUACCAUCCUGGCCGAGUUCGCUGGUGAAGAAGAAGUGAAUCGCUUCUUAGCCCAAGGCCAGGCGCUGCCACCCACUUCCAGCUGGCAGUCCAGCAGCGCGUCCAGCCAGCCGCGGCUCAGCGCAGCGGGCAGCUCCCAUGGCCUGGUACGCAGCGACGCUGGCCACUGGAACGCCCCGUGCCUGGGUGGCAAGGGGAGCAGUGAGCUGCUGUGGGGCGGGGUGCCCCAGUACUCCAGCAGCCUGUGGGGCCCGCCCAGCGCCGACGACAGCAGGGUGAUAGGCAGCCCCACGCCGCUAACCACCCUGCUGCCUGGGGACCUGCUCAGCGGGGAGUCCCUGUAGGCUCUGCCAUCAUCAGCACCAGGAGAGCCGACCCCUCCCGGGACCCCUCCCGGCUGGGCGGCCCCACAGACCCGCUGGAACCCAGCAGCGGCCGCCCUUUUGAGUACCUCUGUCCAGGACUGAAGACGAACCUUGGCCGCAGUCCUUGCGAACUGUUCGCAAAACAGUGCGGGCUGCGGUGGGUCAGCGUCACAUGCUAAUGACAGGAUGUUCCUCGUAGCUUUUUAUUUUGUGCGUCUUAUGUUUGUAUAGUGUGUUGUCAUUUUGAUUUUUUUUUUUUUUUUAAGUAUAAAAGCUGCUUAGAAUAGUUCUAUCAUGAAGGGCACUUUUCAGAUUGUGGGCUGGAAAGGGUUAUUUUAUCUGUGGGGGAGGGAGGGAGACGUGAAGCCUAUUUAAAAUGAGCCUGUGACGAUUAUGCACAUGACCAGAGGCGGCCGGUAAUCAGGGCAGAGUCUGGUGUGGACCGCCGGGCGCAGAGCGGCUCCGCGGCGGGAGCUGAGCGGAAGGCGCGGGCUGCGAUCUGCUCUCUGUUCCCCUGGAUCCGCCUAUGCACAUUACCCUUGUUUCAUUACUUUUUCAUGUCAUUUUUUUAUCCCAAAAAAUAUUUUUUAAAAGUUAAAAAAAGACAUAUCAAACAUGCAAAUACUUGAAUCCAGCAGGCCAAUAGUGAAAUGUGAACACUUUCUAAUUCUACACUUCCAGGUUGACAUCAGUACACAGAAACAGGCUCUAGGAAAAAUUUCUAAGUUCAUAGCCUACGUGUGUGUAUGUGUGCGUGUUGAAACAGAAGUGUGUGUGUGUGUGCAUGUGUGGCGCGUGCUCCUGCACGGCGUGCAGUUUUCUGUGUUUGUGUGUUUGAAAGCGUGUGAGGAUUUAACUGUGGGUUUUCCCUUGUAUUCAGUAUACGCUUUUUUUUUGGCGCAUUGGUCAAACGGUUGUUAUUAUUAGCUUCUAACUUUGCACUGAGUGUCCUCGCCCUUCCUUUAGCUAAUCCUAUACAUUACAGAGAAUUCCUAGGACAGGGCUGGCGACAAUUCAUGUGUAAAUGUUUACUCAAGGACUCUGUGACUGCGUUUAAAAAGUACAGUGUAUAUCUCUGGAGAAAUAACAUGUAUACCUACCUUUAGCAGCUUUUUAUUGUGGACUAAUGCAAGAAAAUUAUUACCAGAGUAUUGCACCAUUUUUCCAUUUGGAAUAUAAAGUUAAAGAGAAAAAAAAAAAAAACUGUUGUUGAACUGUGGCCAUAGAUACUUGUAAAGAAUGGAUGGUUCCGUGGAAGGAACAGAAACAAGCACUUGGGCGUGGGUUGUGACUGCUUUUGGGGGAGCCUGGGGUUUGGGCUCCCACCUGUUUACAGACCUUUUUUUCUCCUUCAGACUUUAAAAUUUUAAAAAUUUAAAAAGGAAUUAAAAAAAAAAAAAGACUUCCGUCGUAAAGAAACCUAUUUUCAGAAUGCAGAUGCGUUCCUUCAGAGCUCUGGGACGGGACAGUGUUGUUCCCUCGGCCAUCGUCGUGGACUCUGUCGAUUGCUUUCGCCCCUUCGUCAAGGUGACAGGCGUUGUGGCCACUGUCUUGCACAUGCCGGACGCGCUCUCAGGAAAGCCAGGGCUCCCGAGGGCAGCUCCACACCAUUUCAUGUAUUUUUAAACCCAACUCCUAGCACUGAAGAUGUUAUUUAAAAAAAAAAAAAACAAAACAAAACAAAAAAAUGAAAAAAAAGAAAAAGAGGAAAAAAAAACACAAAGAAGAAAAAUACCUAAUCUCUAAUGUGUAGCAGUUACAUAUUUACCAAAUAAUGGACUCAAAAGAAAUAGAUGUUUGAAGAGUGCUUUAUAUAUUAAAAAUUGCUUUAUGUUUUAAAAAUGAUCAAUGUUUUGAUUGUUUUGCAAGGAAGAAAGACAAUGGAAUAACAUACCUUCAAGUAUGUUUUAAAAAAUAUAUAUAUGAACAUUGUGCUCCCUGCCUGCUUGAUCAGGAAACUUGUGCAUUACAUUUUUUUAAUUAGCUUUUUAAUGGUUUUAUCAAAACAAAAAAAAUACAAAAAAAAAAAAAAAAGUCCUGCAAGACUGCAGAUCCACAAAAGCUGGUUUUAUAGAGGAUCAUGAACUAUGCACAAACUGGGUUCAAGACUUUUUUUCUCAAGUUUAGUAGGAUAUUUAGAAAAACCAACCUUCCUCAGAGUGACUGCAUCUCAUUGCCAUUACAUGCGUUCUAUAUAUUCGAUGGACAUACACCUGCGUAUGUAUAUCCAAUAUGUGUGCGUGUGAGCAUGCGUGUGCGUAUGUGCGUCCGACAUACCACUUCCCGUGCUGCCGGCGAGCAUUGAGUUGUAGAAAAACUGUUGUUUUAAAAUUGGGGAUGGAAGUCAAGAAUAUGUUUGUUUGUUUUUGGGUUUUGUUGGGUUUGAGGGGUUUUUUGUUUGUUUGUUUUUUGUUUUUUUUACCUUUUAUUUUGAACUUAAUAUGUCUGUAACUCUGAGAUUAAACAACAAGUUCGUGGCUCUUAAUGUUUUCCUCAUAGAAUGUGACUGUUGAAGAACAUGCAUCGAAAGUUGCUUUCGAAAGUACAACGCUUUAUUGAAUCUUAAUAAAUUGCAAUUUUUUUCUUGGCUGUUCAAAGUAAUGUGUUUUUCAUUUUUCAAAAGACACUAUGGAUGUCUACUUUGCACGCUGCGAUUGGGAGAGCUGUCCCGCUGCAUGCGUUCCCUCUGUAAUUUCCUCAGAGCUCACAUACGUACCUCUCUCACGAGUGAACUCAGAUUUUCCAUUGUUUUGCUUUAUUCUAUCAUUUGCUUUGUGGUUUUGCUGUAAAUAUUGAAAUCUUAAUCAUCAUCGAGAGGCACAGCCAAGCUUUCCAGCUCUCCACCCCCGUGGCCCAUCCAAGUCUGUUCAUCUGGUAACUUCUGUUGUCUGGGACGGCAGCAAGAAGAUGCCGGGGCUUGCCUGGAGUCCUGGCAGAGGAGUGCCACUCACUUUUGCCUAGGGUCCAGUUGGGGCUUAAAAAAUAUUUGGAGAGAAGAGUAAUGAGGAUUUUUUGUGUUUCCUAGACAUUUUAUGCAUCUAUUUUUGUAAAAUCACCUUCGCUAACUUUCACCAAGCACUUUGAGCACAGUGGAACUUCAGAAGCACAACCAGCCUAACCCCAGAAUCUCAGGUGGCACAGCUAGAAAUUGAGUCCCUUCCUAGGACACUGGCCGUGGCCUUCAGGGUGACCAGUCAGUGCCACCGGGUUGGCAUUGGUGUUACAGACAGGCCUCUGAAGACAAACCGAGCACCCCAGCGGCCCCUCAAACUAAGCAAGGAUCUUUUUUCUGUCUGCGCUCCCUGGGGCAAGGUCAAAGGUGGACCCGCCCACUGUGGGUCAAUUCCUUCGAAAAGAUGGGACCCGCACCCCCGCCACAGGCUGGCCCCCCCCCACCCAUGGGGAAGGUGGUGUGCUGCUGGCUCUGACCAUACUCUUUUGGAAAUUGAGAAGGAAAGCAUUGAGUGGGACCUAAUCCGGAGAAGAAAUUAAAGACCAGAAAAAGAAGGAAGCUGGGAAUGAAACUCAAAAUGCACUUGAACCUGGAAGCGGCAACCCUCAGCUCUGCGCGGCCGAGCCUCAGCAAGAGUUCGUUUUGUGCCUGAGUUACUACUACAGGGGCAAACUGUACCCGUGCCUGUGCGCUGGGAGAACAAGGUCAGCGCCCAAGGGUGUGCAAAGGAUGUGGCAGGCUUCAUGGAGGAGGUGGCAUUUGCCCUGGGCCUGGGAGACCAGGUUGGAUUUUGACAGACUGGGAACUCGGGGGACAGGAGGGCAGCACAGUGUAAGCUAAAGCCCUGUGUAGGGACCCCACGCAAAGACCUCGUGGGCCUGGGUGUCCAGGGCACCAUUUCCACCCAUGGGUGAAAAAGAGGCUUGAGGAAGACAACAGGUUCUUCACCUGCAUCUGUGGAUAUAUAUUUUUUUAAGUUUAUUAAAUUUUUUUUUAAAUGGCA